ACCCAGCGCAGUGACUGCGGCCCAGCCCGGCGCUCCCCGCAGUCGGGGCGGGGGGACUCUGGCGAGCUUCCCGCGCUCUUGGGAACGGAUAGAUUGUUUUAAAGGAUCCUGCGUUUUUCUGAACGUCAUUCUCCGCUCUACGUACUCAGCAUUACCACUAGAUGGAGCCCUGGCGAUCGCUUGCAUCAUUUUUAGACCCAUAAAAUUCUCGGUGAAAGGCAUCAAGUUAUCAGCAGAUGUCAAACCAUUUGUCCCCAGAUUUGCCGGGCUCAAUGUGGCAUGGUUAGAGUCCUCAGAAGCAUGUGUCUUCCCCAGCUCUGCAGCCACAUACUAUCCGUUUGUUCAGGAACCACCAGUGACAGAGCAGAAAAUAUAUACUGAAGACAUGGCCUUUGGAGCUUCAACUUUUCCACCUCAGUAUUUAUCUUCUGAGAUAACUCUUCAUCCAUAUGCCUAUUCUCCUUAUACCCUUGACUCCACACAGAAUGUUUACUCAGUGCCUGGCUCCCAGUAUCUUUAUAACCAACCCAGUUGUUACCGAGGUUUUCAAACAGUGAAGCAUCGAAAUGAGAACACAUGCCCUCUCCCACAAGAAAUGAAAGCUCUGUUUAAGAAGAAAACCUAUGAUGAGAAAAAAACGUAUGAUCAGCAAAAGUUUGACAGUGAAAGGGCUGAUGGAACUAUAUCAUCUGAGAUAAAAUCAGCUAGAGGUUCACAUCAUUUGUCCAUUUACGCUGAGAAUAGUUUGAAAUCAGAUGGUUACCAUAAGCGAACAGACAGGAAAUCCAGAAUCAUUGCAAAAAAUGUAUCUACCUCCAAACCUGAGUUUGAAUUUACCACACUGGACUUUCCUGAACUGCAAGGUGCAGAGAACAAUAUGUCAGAGAUACAGAAGCAACCCAAGUGGGGACCUGUCCACUCUGUCUCUACCGACAUUUCUCUUCUAAGAGAAGUAGUAAAACCAGCUGCAGUGUUAUCAAAGGGUGAAAUAGUGGUGAAAAAUAACCCAAAUGAAUCUGUAACUGCUAAUGCCGCUACCAAUUCUCCUUCAUGUACAAGAGAGUUAUCUUGGACACCAAUGGGUUAUGUUGUUCGACAGACAUUAUCUACAGAACUGUCAGCAGCCCCUAAAAAUGUUACUUCUAUGAUAAACUUAAAGACCAUUGCUUCAUCAGCAGAUCCUAAAAAUGUUAGUAUACCAUCUUCUGAAGCUUUAUCUUCGGAUCCUUCCUACAACAAAGAAAAACACAUUAUUCAUCCUACCCAAAAGUCUAAAGCAUCACAAGGUAGUGACCUUGAACAAAAUGAAGCCUCAAGAAAGAAUAAGAAAAAGAAAGAAAAAUCUACAUCAAAAUAUGAAGUCCUGACAGUUCAAGAGCCUCCAAGGAUUGAAGAUGCCGAGGAAUUUCCCAACCUGGCAGUUGCAUCUGAAAGAAGAGACAGAAUAGAGACACCGAAAUUUCAAUCUAAGCAGCAGCCACAGGAUAAUUUUAAAAAUAAUGUAAAGAAGAGCCAGCUUCCAGUGCAGUUGGACUUGGGGGGCAUGCUGACAGCCCUGGAGAAGAAGCAGCACUCUCAGCAUGCAAAGCAGUCCUCCAAACCAGUGGUAGUCUCAGUUGGAGCAGUGCCAGUCCUUUCCAAAGAAUGUGCAUCAGGGGAGAGAGGCCGCCGCAUGAGUCAAAUGAAGACCCCGCACAAUCCCUUGGACUCCAGCGCCCCACUGAUGAAGAAAGGGAAGCAGAGGGAGAUCCCCAAGGCCAAGAAGCCAACCUCACUGAAGAAGAUUAUUUUGAAAGAACGGCAAGAGAGAAAGCAGCGUCUCCAAGAAAAUGCUGUGAGUCCAGCUUUUACCAGUGAUGACACACAAGAUGGAGAGAGUGGUGGUGAUGACCAGUUUCCCGAGCAGGCAGAGCUGUCAGGGCCAGAGGGGAUGGACGAACUGAUCUCCACUCCUUCGGUUGAGGACAAGUCUGAAGAGCCACCAGGCACAGAGCUCCAGAGGGACACAGAGGCCUCCCACCUUGCUCCCAAUCACACCACCUUCCCUAAGAUCCACAGCCGCAGAUUCAGGGAUUACUGCAGCCAGAUGCUUAGUAAAGAAGUGGAUGCUUGUGUUACCGACCUACUCAAAGAACUGGUCCGUUUCCAAGACCGUAUGUACCAGAAAGAUCCAGUCAAGGCCAAGACUAAACGUCGACUUGUGUUGGGGUUGAGGGAGGUUCUCAAACACCUGAAGCUCAAAAAACUGAAAUGUGUCAUUAUUUCUCCCAACUGUGAGAAGAUACAGUCAAAAGGUGGGCUGGAUGACACUUUGCACACAAUUAUUGAUUAUGCCUGUGAGCAGAACAUUCCCUUUGUGUUUGCUCUCAACCGCAAAGCUCUGGGGCGCAGUUUGAAUAAGGCAGUUCCUGUCAGUGUGGUGGGGAUCUUCAGCUAUGAUGGGGCCCAGGAUCAGUUCCACAAGAUGGUUGAGCUGACAGUGGCGGCCCGACAGGCGUACAAGACCAUGCUGGAGAAUGUGCAGCAGGAGCUGGUGGGAGAGCCCAGGCCUCAGGCACCUCCCAGCCUACCCACACAGGGCCCCAGCUGCCCUGCAGAAGAUGGCCCCCCAGCCCUGAAAGAAAAAGAAGAGCCACACUACAUUGAAAUCUGGAAAAAACAUCUGGAAGCAUACAGUGGAUGUACCCUGGAGCUAGAAGAAUCCUUGGAGGCUUCAACCUCUCAAAUGAUGAAUUUGAAUUUAUGAGAGUUCUUGCCUGUGUGUCUGUAUUUUGGCAGAGCAAAGAAAGACUCAGAAAUUCAUCCUCAUAACUCCAUUUCCCAGUAGAACACUCCACAUUACGAAAACUUCAAGUAUGUAAUUAUUUUGUUAAGUGUGAAAGUGCUUGAAAUCCAGACUUCAGGAGAAGAGACAGAAAACAGCACCAAGAAUAUAAGCCUAAAGCCCAUAGCAUUUCACUCAUCAGUUUGUAGUGGUUGAAGCCACACCCAAAGCAAGAACCACAGUGAGCUGAUGGAUAUUUUACAGGAAAACUUCAGGUUAUGAGUAUGUGAUGGUUCCGUGAGCAAGACUGGCAUCCUUGGCUGGAUGGGCAAGCACACACCUCACAGGCAGCUGGGCCUCUCGACUUGGGGUGCGGAGGGGGAACGUGUGGAGACAACCAGGGUGUCUCCAGCAUCUUCAGGACACCUGUUGUGAUGGAUCCUGAAGGAAUUAGCAGGCGAUGUAUGCUGAUCCCACACAAAGGCUGGUAGAGAAUUUGUCCAGCUCCAGAAAGAGGGGAUGCAAAACAGGUCAUUGUCACACUGCUGGGAAGACACUCAGUAUUUGCUAGGAUCACCAGAGGGGUGCGGCUUGACUUUUAACAGAGGCUUUGGUUUUAUGAUAGACAUGAAAACUGUCAUUCAACAGACAAGAAGAGACGUGUGUGUAAGAUUAAAGGCUGAGUAGCUUUAGGACAAGUUCACACACACAGUGACACAGUCUUCAGAGAUACAGCUUUAAUAAUUAGAGACUUGAAAGCAGGUAGAACAAAACACUCAUGAGACUCAUUCCAUCGUCAAGAAAUUUAAUAUGGCACCAGGAGAUUUGCAUAAUUGACCUAUUUGGCUUUCUGCAUCAAGUUUGGUGUCCUGUUGCAGAAGCUGAGCAUUGACGGGACAGAGGCAUAAACUGCAGCGCUUGAUAAAAUAGAGCCCAGUAUUCUGAGGUUAGUGAAGAAAACACAAAGACUUGACAGAUGCACUCCCAGAUCGCAUCUCACAGUCAUUCAAGGUUUAGGGCAAGGCAUUUCCAUGUGGAGUCUCACCUUUUCUUGUCCCAGUCAUGCAUCUUGGAGUUCCUUGGCUAAGUCUGCAGGGAGGAGAAGCAGCAGGCUUGAUUUGCAUCAAUAAAAGCAGCGAUCUGUGCUGGCCAUGCUAACCCUGUUGGCUAUUAGGGGGUGGGGGCACUCUGUCAAGGGGAGUCACUGGGACGGUGUAGGAUCAGCCUUCAGAGCCUGCUGCCUGACCGUAGAGGAGGAACCUGCACACACCCUGCUGUUUUAGUUCACGAGCAGCUAUCAAAGCCUGUUAGCCAUCCUGGUUACCUGCUUGUGCCAGACAGAACUUACUGUCCCAGGUAAGCACCUAAUUUUUUAAGUCUUAGUUCCUGUCACAGGCCCACUUGGGUUCCAGGCUUCUCCACUGUCCCGCCUCUGCCCAUCAGGUGGUGGCCCAAUGGCUGUGUUCAGAGCAGGCUUGGGCAAGACAGUUCACAGUUGUGGGGGACCAGGCCUUCUCCGGGGGUGGCUGUGGUCAGUGGCAGCAGGGUCUUGUUGGGGUUGAGGUCGGUGUCAGGGACUCCUUCCUGGUGGCUACAGGGUGUCCUUGCUACAGCUUUCCUGAAAGAACAAUGUGGUCUUUGAAUCCUUGGUGGAACGGAUGGGCCUUUCCUGCUCUGCAGCCCAGUCUGUCUCAUAGCCCAUCCCAGGCAGAGCACUCAAGGCCUCAGCCCCCUGUUGUGGUUCCCCUCCUUGGAGUCUAAAGAUCCAAAUGCCAGGAGUGGUUCUCCCAUAUGUGACAGGAAGGCAGAGCAGCAGCGCAUUCACUCCACUCCCAGAUUGUGCUGAGAGGCAGGAGGGCUGGAGAGAGGGAGCCUGUGUGUGCUGAAGUACAGAGGAUCAGCUGUAAAUGCCCAGCCUUUGGUGGCAACAGUUCGGGGGUGUACUGCUGGCAGCCACGUAACCCACACACUUUAAUGCACUCAUUUGAGUGCUGCAGACCCCACCGCAGGUGGUAGCACACAGUGAUGAAUCCCUGCCUUUGCCUUCUGUAUCGGCUAUUUAGGAGCCGGGGCUGGACAACUUUGUCUCCGUGGGGAGACAGGGAGCCUCUAGGGAGCCUCUGCCCCACUGCCUGCAGCUUCCAUGCUGUAGCCCAGUUCCUGCCAGGGCUUAGCUCAGGAAGCCACUCCCCCUGACCCCUCCAACAGGUGCCUCAGGUGAGGCAUCCAGCCAGGAGCUACCUGGAGGGUUCCCCAUCUGUCCAGGUUUCCUGCCCUCCUCAAAGGAGUGGCUGGCUGAGUGCUCUGUACAGAGAAUGGGGUGGUCGUGGGGGCCCAUCUAACUAGACAGCCCCACCUGUGAGUCCCUCCCAGUCUCGCCUCCCUUCAGUCUCUUUUAAGGGCUGGGGCCAGAUGCCCCUUGAUCUCCUGCAGUCUCAGCAACAAGACGUGGGAUUUCCCCCCCCAGUGUUGCAGAUUUCAUAAAGGAAACUGCUCCGGGGCUAAGAGGGAACAAGUGGGGUCCAUGCUGAAUGGGGCCCUUGAAAGAUCCACUGGAUGUGGCAGGUGCCCUGCCCCUGGCUCCAGCCCUCCUUUCUUUGCCCGGCUGCGGCCACUUACCCACGCCUUCCUCCAGCUCUGCAUCAUCCGGUCGUGCUCCCCAGCCACAGCCCUCCAGGCAGAGAGCUCUCUGGUCCACCUCUCCUGGUGGGUCACUUCUGGAAAACAAGCAGGGUCCCCAGGUCAAAGCUCUGUGGGCCUUUAUGGCACCCUUGAUGCCCACUGGCCACCUUUCUCAAUGGAAAGCCAAUAAAACCCAAACCCAGAAUGCCACCGUGCAAGCAUGCUUUCCAGCUGUUUUUUUCACUGCCAUUGUAAAUAGUGAAAAAUUACCUCAUAAAAGGGUAACAGUGGGCAUGGGAAUCACUUACCAGGUCUCAUCACAGCAACCUGCACCUUCGAAGUCUUGUUCCCUGCUGAGGAGAGGACAGAGCAGCGAUACUCAGCGCUUUCCCUGAUGGCGUCCUGCAGCCAGCUGAGUGCAUGGGCCCUGCCAUCGGGCAGUGCAUGGGUCUGCACAGGGACACAGGUCUCCAGAGCUCGCCCAUUCUUCUCCCAGACAAAGCGAAUGUCUGCAGGACCUGGGGACACAGACCGUUUCCACCUCUGAGUCCACAUUUAGGACCCAAAGAAGCUGCCCCAUGAGGGUGCAGGGGGGUUACCUCUGCUGUCCCAGUUGGACCUGAAGUGACUUGGGACAACUUCCAAUUCAGUCCCUGGGACUGCCCUGGAGGUGGCUUCCCCAUGGCCAGCGGGAGCCUUGGCCUUGGCCCGUCCUGUGGACUUCCUGCUCUUUGACCUUAAUUGCCAUUUUUCAAAGCACACCUGUGUGGCCUGUGUCCCCUAGGACCCCCUUUCUUGCAGCGCUGUGCUGGUUUCUUACAGAAUGGUUCUGGGCCUUGGAACAGCAUCCCACCCCACCAUGGCCCUGCUGCCACACACAUGUCCUGUGACCACAUGGACAGAGACAUCCCAAGGCUCUGCCAUCACCAGGGCCACAGCAUGGAGAGGCCCAGAGCUCGGCCAGCUGUGUGCAGAGGGGGCUGGGCCAGAGUGGGGACCAUGAGGGCCUGUCUCUCCAAUUGAGACACUGGGGUGGGCUUGGAGGGGAGUAGAUGCCACAGGCUGGAGAGCUCAGACCCUGGCAGGGGCCAGGCCCUGCAGAAUUACACUAGGACUGCCGAGUGCAGCACAUCCAGGAUGGGCUUCCAGCCUUGAGCAUGGACUCUGGGCCCGACAUUGGCCACUUCUGCCGCAAACCUCUGUUGUUUUUCUCUGGGCUUUUGAUCUUAAUUACUUAUUGAAGAAAGUAGAGAGGCCAGUUACUUCACACACACUCAGACCAUCUGUUGCAACCUGCCAGGGUGGAGCCUGGCUGGCCUCAGCUUGUCUGAUGGAGAGAUCAGGAGGGUGGGCGAGGCAGAGACGUUCCCCUGUGGCCCAGGCUGCCUCGCCUGGGGAGGCCAGCCUCAUCCCAGGGCAAGAAGUCUGCGCGGCCAACCCUGAGGGCUACUCCUAGACACUAUUUGUUCCAGGUGGCUGGGGUGGGGCUGUGAAAACCAGAAUGUUGGGGGUUUUGGGCGGGGGGGAGGGGCACAAGUAAGUUCUGGUCAGCAGGUCACCUCCCGGCCUUCCUUGCUCGUGAAGUCUGUUGGCCCUCCAGGGGCUGCUGGCCAUGUUGGGACAGGCUCAACUCCCUGUUCUUACUGAAGGAAAAACAAGCACAUCCAUUUUGAUCUGCUUCGCACACUGGCUUCCACUCAAAUGCAGAAAGGGCUGAGGGGGGCCACAGUCCCACUAAGCUCCAGCCCCAGAGCGUACAGACCCUGGAGUUGAGCUGGGAGGGCCAGGCCAGGCCCUGGAGGGCAGGUGAGGGGGUGCAGGUGCUCCUUCUGUCUCUGAAGCUCCUGCUUGUGGUGGGGCUGGGGAGGCCGGCCAGCCUACUCUGCUGCUUCUGUCUCCCUCAGGCACAGCCUGCAUCAGGCCAGGCACCCCAGCAGCGUGGACUGGGGUGACACCCACCUGCUGCCUAGCGACCCGGCUCCCUGACCAGCACCUGCCCUUCCUCGAGGCCCACCAAGGCCCCCAAAUGGGCCAUGGGCCACCUAGACCAGUGCCGGCCAUGGCCUCUGCUUGACCAUGACACCUCGUAAGAAUUGGUCUUUAGAAGUUAGAUUUGCCCUAGAUGUCCAUCAACCUCACAAUGACAAAAUGAAGUGUGGCUUCAUGGAGAAUGCUUAGUAGUGAAAAGGAAGGAGUUCAGAACACUGAGCAGGUAAAACAAAUUCCAGAGCCAAAAGAGUCCAAAGUACCUGCACACACAAAAACUGGCCUUGUUCUCAGGUGUAGGGGCAGAGGUGCAUCCAGUUACAGGUAUUAAAUGGUGUGGGUGGACCCACGCUCCCCUCCCUGGGCAGGACAGUAGUGGCCAGAGAGCUUUCCAUUUCUGUGGCACAUGCUGGACUUUUGAAAAGAAGAGAUCGCCAGUUUAAUGAAGCUGACUUUAGUAAUGCAUUUUCCCUGCUUUACUGACUGUGGCAUCUGCUCAUCUUUGUCCGGUCUCUUGGUCAACAAUUCCCCACUGUCCAGGAUCACCAGAGAAUGCUCCUCCCAAGGACUUGACCAAGCUCAGACCCUUUAGCUGGGCAGUCCUAGGAAUGAGUCCCGAGGCAAGGAUGGGCCCAGUGAAGCCCUGUUUCUAUCAGUGAGGAGUUGGGAAAUGUCCAAGAAGGGGGCCACAAGUCACUCAUUCGAAGUGCCAUCGAAGAAUAUUCAGCAACACAGAAAAAUAAGUGAAACAAUAUCUAGGAAUGUGUGCAUAUAUGUACACACCCAUGUAUACAUGUGUGAACGUAGAUAGUCAUGGCCCAAAAAUGGCUGGGAUGCUGGUGGUAACUACCUCUGGAUGGUUAAAUUUGGGAUUGUUUAAAUUUUUUCUUUAUACUUCCCUGGAGUUUCCAAACUUAUAACAAACAAGCAUUGCUUUUAUAAUAAUAAUUUUUUAUAAAAGUGUUACUUUGAAGGAAACAUUCUGUAAACUCAAGGAAAUUCAGAAGGUGCUCCAAAACUGUUUUGCCUGGCGGCCCAUCUGGCCCUGGCCUGGUGGACAAGCCCUUGUGAACAGGUUUGGUUUUUGUGCAGAAUUUAAAAAAAAACAAAACUUAACACUCUAUAAUUUGUUUUUUCCCACUCAAAAUGUUUUGGACUCUGGCCACAGAUAAUUCCAUGUAUCUAUCUACAAAUAUAAGUACAUAUUACAUAGAUGUACAAACAUAUGUCUCUAUGUACAUCUAGGUGCCCAUCAACUGGGGAAUAGAUAUUCCCUUUCCCAGCUGAUGGGCAUCCAGGUAAAAUCUCAUUUUAAGAAACAGAUUUUUUUGAGCUGUUAUGAUCAAGUAACACUUUUCUUUGAACAGACAGUGAAGUGAGUUCUAUAAAAGCCCGGUCUCCUCCCUCAUGUGACCUGCACCAAGAACCACCCAGGGGACUGGAGUCACUGAGUCACAGGAGCCUCUGGAAGGUUCUCAUGACCAAGCCCUUGAGACUAAGAAUCUGGGUGGCCUAAGCUGGAUUGGAUUAAUCACCCAACGCCCCAUCAUGGGACCACUGACUGCAAAACCCUCAAAGCUCUACACUCUUGGGGUGUGAGCAGAAACAGACACGUGCUUACCACUGCUAACAGGCAUCAGUAAAUACUAUUUAAAUACAUGCUUGAUCAUCAUAAGACAUUAAAGAUGUUAAAGAAGUA